GCACUCGCAGGGCCCGUGGCGGUUCAGGCGCCAGAGCUGGCCGAUCGGCGUUGGCCGCCGACAUGACGCCCGAGGACCCAGAGGAAACCCAGCCGCUUCUGGGGCCUCCUGGCGGCAGCGCGCCCCGCGGCCGCCGCGUCUUCCUCGCCGCCUUCGCCGCUGCCCUGGGCCCACUCAGCUUCGGCUUCGCGCUCGGCUACAGCUCCCCGGCCAUCCCUAGCCUGCAGCGCGCCGCGCCCCCGGCCCCGCGCCUGGACGACGCCGCCGCCUCCUGGUUCGGGGUGAGGCCCCGGGCUCGCUCCUCCCGCCCUGGGACCCCACGCCCUCCUCUCGGGACGGGCAUCGGGACCCUCCGCCCCCCACCCUUCCCCUCGGGACAGGCAUCGGGCCCCGCCGCCACCACCUUUCCCCACGAGACAGGCAUUGGGCCUCUCUGCCCCCCAUCCCUUCCCUCGGGACGGGCAUCGAGCCCCUCAGCCCCCACCCCUCCCCUCGGGACGAGCACCGGGCCCCUCAGCCCCCUACCCCUCCCCUCGGGACGGGCGCGGGGCCCCGGCUCUUUUACCUCUGAGCCCGCGGGGAGUGGGUGGAGGGGGAGGAUGGGCUGCGGCUUCGGCGCCCCCUCCUCAGCAGCCGCCCGCCUCCAGGCUGUCGUGACCCUGGGUGCCGCGGCGGGGGGAGUGCUGGGCGGCUGGCUGGUGGACCGCGCCGGGCGCAAGCUGAGCCUCUUGCUGUGCUCCGUGCCCUUCGUGGCCGGCUUUGCCGUCAUCACCGCGGCCCAGGACGUGUGGAUGCUGCUGGGGGGCCGCCUCCUCACCGGCCUGGCCUGCGGUGUUGCCUCCCUAGUGGCCCCGGUCUACAUCUCCGAAAUCGCCUACCCAGCAGUCCGGGGGUUGCUCGGCUCCUGUGUGCAGCUAAUGGUCGUCGUCGGCAUCCUCCUGGCCUACCUGGCAGGCUGGGUGCUGGAGUGGCGCUGGCUGGCUGUGCUGGGCUGCGUGCCCCCCUCCCUCAUGCUGCUUCUCAUGUGCUUCAUGCCCGAGACCCCGCGCUUCCUGCUGACUCAGCACAGGCGCCAGGAGGCCAUGGCCGCCCUGCGGUUCCUGUGGGGCUCCGAGCAGGGCUGGGAAGACCCCCCCAUCGGGGCUGAGCAGAGCUUUCACCUGGCCCUGCUGCGGCAGCCCGGCAUCUACAAGCCCUUCAUCAUCGGCGUCUCCCUGAUGGCCUUCCAGCAGCUGUCGGGGGUCAACGCCGUCAUGUUCUAUGCAGAGACCAUCUUUGAAGAGGCCAAGUUCAAGGACAGCAGCCUGGCCUCGGUCGUCGUGGGUGUCAUCCAGGUGCUGUUCACAGCUGUGGCGGCUCUCAUCAUGGACAGAGCAGGGCGGAGGCUGCUCCUGGUCUUGUCAGGUGUGGUCAUGGUGUUCAGCACGAGUGCCUUCGGCGCCUACUUCAAGCUGACCCAGGGUGGCCCUGGCAACUCCUCGCACGUGGCCAUCUCGGCGCCUGUCUCUGCACAGCCUGUUGAUGCCAGCGUGGGGCUGGCCUGGCUGGCCGUGGGCAGCAUGUGCCUCUUCAUCGCCGGCUUUGCGGUGGGCUGGGGGCCCAUCCCCUGGCUCCUCAUGUCAGAGAUCUUCCCUCUGCAUGUCAAGGGCGUGGCGACAGGCAUCUGCGUCCUCACCAACUGGCUCAUGGCCUUUCUCGUGACCAAGGAGUUCAGCAGCCUCAUGGAGGUCCUCAGGCCCUAUGGAGCCUUCUGGCUUGCCUCCGCUUUCUGCAUCUUCAGUGUCCUUUUCACUUUGUUCUGUGUCCCUGAAACUAAAGGAAAGACUCUGGAACAAAUCACAGCCCAUUUUGAGGGGCGAUGACAGCCACUCACUAGGGGAUGGAGCAAGCCUGUGACUCCAAGCUGGGCCCAAGCCCAGAGCCCCUGCCUGCCCCAGGGGAGCCAGAAUCCAGCCCCUUGGAGCCUUGGUCUGCAGGGUCCCUCCUUCCUGUCAUGCUCCCUCCAGCCCAUGACCCGGGGCUAGGAGGCUCACUGCCUCCUGUUCCAGCUCCUGCUGCUGCUCUGAGGACUCAGGAACACCUUCGAGCUUUGCAGACCUGCGGUCAGCCCUCCAUGCGCAAGACUAAAGCAGCGGAAGAGGAGGUGGGCCUCUAGGAUCUUUGUCUUCUGGCUGGAGGUGCUUUUGGAGGUUGGGUGCUGGGCAUUCAGUCGCUCCUCUCACGCGGCUGCCUUAUCGGGAAGGAAAUUUGUUUGCCAAAUAAAGACUGACACAGAAAAUCAGGUCAGUGUCUCUGGGCUUUGUGCAAGCUCAGUUUGAAAAGGGUUUAUUCCCAUCACUGCCCAGGACACCCUGUGGCUUUACUUGCUCAUGGUCAGCCAAGCUUACCCUUCACACUGAGAAGUCAUUUCUGGCUACUUCCUUGGGCUCAGUUCCCUGGGUCAUCAGCCAUCAAAUCUUGUUGAGUUUAAAAAAUAAACAGCAAAAAAAAACAAAACAAAACAAAAAAAAA